AGUCUCCGCAUCUGCUCCUUCAUCCAGUGCCGCAGCCGGAAAACCGCAGCGGCGGCGGCGGCGGCUGAGGGGGAACGAUCCAGCGAGCUGCAGAAAGGGGGGCAGGAAAAAAUUACAAGGACAUUACUGAUAAGACAGGAACUGAGAGCUUGGGAUUCGCGGCCUCUCCCCGGCCACCACCUUCGCCGUCAGCAAGGGAGGAAGACCCGGGAGACGGCAGCGGCGACGGCGGCAGGGGAAGGAGGAGACGGCGACGGGAGGGAGCACAGAGGAGGGGACGGGCCGGCGGCGGCCUGUGAGCCGCAGUGAUUUUGACGUUUUCCGCUGCUGCGUCUCCGGCGGGCAGGGGCCGGGCUGCGCUGGGUGGGCCAGCUCGCCCCGCGCUUCCCCCUCGUCCUGCUCGUCCCUCCGCCCACCCGGGGCCUGAGGGGUCUCCCCGCUCCGAGGGAAGGGGAGAGGGAGGCGAGGGCGUGCGGGCAUCGCGAUGGCGGGGACAUUUUCCACAACGUGAUUGUUGAAGGCUCCCCCCAUCCCCCCUCCCUUAAAAUUCCGGGCCCUUCCAGCCUCCACCCUCCCCCAAGCCCGUGUGACUAAACCGAGACAAAGGGGAGGCGGCCUCGCUCACACGCGGGCUCGCGGGGCGGGUGGCUCGGAGGGGCGCGGGCACGGGGCGGACCUCGCGCGGACGGACGGACGGAGACGGCGCCGCCACAUUCCUAUGCCCGGGAGCGGCGGCGGCGGCGGCGGCGGCUCCCGCGGGAGGCGGCAGGCGCGCGGCGCGGACAGCUGAGCUUCUCCUCCGUCGGCGCCCGGGCGGACAUCGCCCGGGCCCCGAUGGUUUGAGCUUGCUUCUCCCUCCCUCCCGACCCCCGUGGUGGCGAGGCCACGCCAUGUGAAGGUUAGGGCCGGGACAUCCCGAGGAGCCGCGGUGAAAGAUGGGGGAUGCUGCAGACCCCAGGGAGAUGAGAAAGACGUUCAUUGUUCCAGCCAUCAAGCCUUUUGACCACUAUGAUUUCUCCAGGGCCAAAAUCGCCUGCAAUCUGGCCUGGCUGGUGGCCAAAGCCUUUGGGACAGAAAAUGUGCCAGAGGAACUUCAAGAACCAUUUUACACAGAUCAGUAUGACCAGGAACACAUCAAACCACCUGUUGUUAAUUUGCUUCUAUCGGCUGAACUAUACUGUCGUGCUGGGAGUCUCAUUCUCAAGAGUGAUGCUGCAAAACCCCUUUUGGGCCAUGAUGCUGUAAUCCAGGCUUUAGCACAGAAAGGUCUUUAUGUCACUGACCAGGAAAAAUUGGUAACUGAACGAGAUCUCCACAAGAAACCCAUACAGAUGAGUGCACAUUUGGCCAUGAUCGAUACCCUCAUGAUGGCUUAUACUGUAGAAAUGGUCAGUAUAGAAAAAGUAAUUGCGUGUGCUCAGCAGUAUUCAGCUUUUUUUCAAGCCACAGAUCUGCCCUAUGAUAUUGAGGACGCUGUCAUGUACUGGAUAAAUAAGGUAAAUGAACAUUUGAAAGACAUAAUGGAACAAGAACAAAAACUGAAAGAACAUCACACAGUUGAAGCUCCAGGAGGUCAAAAGUCUCCUUCCAAAUGGUUUUGGAAACUGGUUCCAGCUCGUUAUCGGAAAGAGCAAACAUUGCUUAAGCAACUGCCUUGCAUUCCAUUGGUAGAAAAUUUGUUGAAGGAUGGGACAGAUGGCUGUGCAUUAGCUGCCCUUAUUCAUUUUUACUGUCCUGAUGUUGUCAGAUUAGAGGAUAUUUGUUUGAAAGAAACUAUGUCUUUGGCUGAUAGCCUGUAUAAUCUGCAGCUGAUUCAAGAAUUUUGCCAAGAAUACUUGAACCAGUGUUGCCAUUUCACUCUGGAAGAUAUGCUCUAUGCUGCUUCAUCCAUAAAGAGUAAUUAUUUGGUGUUCAUGGCGGAACUGUUCUGGUGGUUUGAAGUGGUGAAGCCGUCUUUUGUACAGCCUCGUGUUGUUCGUCCACAAGGAGCUGAACCUGUAAAAGAUAUGCCUUCAAUUCCUGUCUUGAAUGCUGCCAAAAGAAAUGUCUUAGAUAGUAGUUCUGACUUCCCUUCAAGUGGGGAAGGAGCUACAUUUACACAGUCUCAUCAUCAUUUGCCUUCUAGGUAUUCACGUCCCCAGGCUCAUUCUUCAGCCUCAGGAGGAAUUAGAAGGUCUUCAUCUAUGUCUUAUGUUGAUGGCUUCAUAGGGACAUGGCCCAAAGAGAAAAGAUCAUCAGUGCAUGGCGUAUCAUUUGAUAUUUCUUUUGAUAAAGAAGAUAGUGUACAGAGAUCCACUCCAAACCGAGGAAUCACUCGUUCUAUUAGUAAUGAAGGACUUACUCUGAACAACAGUCAUGUAUCUAAACACAUUAGGAAAAAUUUGUCCUUCAAGCCAAUAAAUGGAGAAGAGGAAGCAGAGAGCAUUGAAGAAGAACUUAAUAUAGAUUCUCACAGUGACCUCAAAUCUUGUGUGCCCCUUAACACAAAUGAACUAAAUUCUAAUGAGAAUAUUCAUUACAAGCUUCCAAAUGGAGCUUUACAAAAUAGAAUACUUCUUGACGAGUUUGGCAAUCAGAUCGAGACACCAAGCAUUGAAGAAGCAUUACAAAUAAUUCAUGAUACUGAAAAAUCUCCUCAUACACCUCAGCCAGACCAAAUUGCUAAUGGCUUCUUUCUUCAUAGUCAAGAAAUGAGUAUCUUAAAUUCAAAUAUCAAGUUAAAUCAAUCUAGUCCUGAUAAUGUAACUGAUACGAAAGGUGCCUUGAGUCCCAUAACUGACAAUACUGAAGUAGACACUGGAAUUCACGUUCCUUCAGAAGAUAUUCCUGAAACUAUGGACGAAGAUUCUUCGUUGAGAGAUUAUACUGUAAGCUUGGACUCUGACAUGGAUGAUGCAUCUAAAUUUCUUCAGGAUUAUGAUAUUCGAACUGGCAACACCAGGGAAGCUUUGAGUCCUUGUCCAAGUACUGUAAGUACCAAGUCUCAGCCAGGCAGCAGUGCUUCUUCUAGUUCUGGAGUUAAAAUGACCAGCUUUGCUGAACAAAAAUUCAGGAAACUGAAUCAUACCGAUGGAAAAAGUAGUGGAAGCAGUUCUCAAAAAACUACACCAGAAGGCUCUGAACUUAAUAUUCCUCAUGUGGUUGCUUGGGCACAAAUUCCAGAAGAAACAGGGCUUCCACAGGGACGGGACACUACCCAGCUGUUGGCCUCUGAAAUGGUGCAUCUUAGGAUGAAACUAGAAGAAAAGAGGCGUGCUAUAGAAGCCCAGAAAAAGAAAAUGGAAGCUGCUUUUACCAAACAGAGACAGAAAAUGGGAAGGACAGCAUUCCUUACUGUAGUGAAAAAGAAAGGGGAUGGGAUAUCUCCUCUACGAGAGGAAGCGGCGGGUGCAGAAGAUGAGAAAGUAUAUACUGAUCGAGCAAAAGAAAAGGAAUCACAAAAAACUGAUGGACAAAGGAGCAAGUCACUGGCAGAUAUAAAAGAGAGCAUGGAGAAUCCUCAAGCCAAAUGGCUAAAGUCUCCAACUACACCUAUUGAUCCUGAGAAGCAGUGGAACCUGGCAAGCCCCUCAGAAGAAACUUUAAAUGAAGGAGAGAUUUUAGAAUAUACCAAAUCCAUUGAAAAGUUAAAUUCAUCCCUGCAUUUUCUACAACAAGAAAUGCAACGCUUGUCACUUCAGCAGGAGAUGUUAAUGCAGAUGAGAGAGCAACAAUCUUGGGUGAUUUCACCUCCACAACCCUCUCCACAGAAACAGAUUCGAGAUUUUAAGCCUUCUAAGCAGGCAGGCCUGUCAUCAGCCAUUGCACCAUUCUCCUCAGACUCCCCUCGUCCUACUCACCCAUCUCCACAGUCUUCUAACAGGAAAAGUGCAUCUUUUUCUGUUAAAAGUCAAAGGACUCCUAGGCCAAAUGAGUUAAAAAUAACACCUUUGAAUCGAACCUUGACACCUCCUCGGUCUGUGGAUAGCCUUCCUCGGUUAAGGAGGUUUUCACCAAGUCAAGUUCCUAUUCAAACUAGGUCAUUUGUAUGUUUUGGGGAUGAUGGAGAACCUCAGUUAAAGGAAUCCAAACCUAAAGAGGAAGUUAAAAAGGAGGAAUUGGAAUCCAAAGGGACUUUGGAACAGCGUGGACAUAAUCCAGAAGAAAAGGAAAUCAAACCUUUUGAGUCAACAGUCUCUGAAGUCCUAUCACUGCCUGUCACAGAGACUGUAUGUCUGACACCAAAUGAGGACCAAUUGAAUCAACCCACAGAACCCCCUCCUAAACCCGUUUUCCCACCCACUGCUCCAAAAAAUGUUAAUCUGAUUGAAGUUUCCCUCUCAGAUUUGAAACCCCCUGAAAAGGCUGAUGUACCUGUUGAAAAAUAUGAUGGAGAAAGUGAUAAAGAACAAUUUGAUGAUGACCAGAAAGUAUGCUGUGGAUUCUUUUUUAAGGAUGAUCAAAAAGCAGAAAAUGAUAUGGCAAUGAAACGGGCAGCUUUGUUGGAGAAAAGAUUAAGAAGGGAAAAGGAAACUCAGCUCCGGAAACAACAGUUGGAAGCAGAAAUGGAGCAUAAGAAGGAGGAAACAAGGCGUAAAACUGAGGAAGAACGUCAGAAGAAAGAAGAUGAGAGAGCACGCAGAGAAUUUAUUAGGCAAGAAUAUAUGAGGCGGAAACAACUGAAACUAAUGGAAGAUAUGGAUACAGUAAUUAAACCCCGUCCUCAAGUAGUAAAACAAAAAAAACAGCGACCAAAAUCUAUUCACAGAGAUCAUAUUGAAUCCCCCAAAACACCAAUAAAGGGUCCUCCAGUCUCUAGCCUUUCUUUGGCAUCGCUGAACACGGGUGAUAACGAGAGUGUACAUUCAGGCAAGAGGACGCCAAGAUCAGAGUCUGUAGAAGGCUUCUUAUCUCCAAGUCGUUGUGGCAGUCGAAAUGGAGAAAAAGACUGGGAGAAUGCAUCAACAACUUCUUCAGUGGCUUCUGGAACAGAAUAUACAGGACCAAAGCUCUACAAAGAACCCAGUGCAAAAUCCAAUAAGCACAUAAUACAAAAUGCUUUAGCUCAUUGCUGUUUGGCUGGAAAAGUAAAUGAAGGUCAGAAGAAAAAAAUACUGGAGGAAAUGGAGAAAUCAGAUGCCAACAACUUCUUAAUCUUGUUCCGGGAUUCAGGAUGCCAGUUCAGAUCUUUAUACACUUAUUGCCCAGAAACUGAAGAAAUCAAUAAACUGACUGGGAUAGGCCCUAAAUCUAUCACUAAAAAAAUGAUUGAAGGACUUUACAAAUAUAAUUCUGACAGGAAACAGUUUAGCCACAUACCCGCUAAAACUUUAUCUGCCAGUGUUGAUGCAAUUACCAUUCAUAGCCAUUUAUGGCAGACCAAAAGACCAGUAACACCCAAAAAACUUUUACCCACUAAGGCAUAGAAGUUGGGAAAUACUUGCUUCAGAACAUUCAUGGUAAAUUUGCACUUCAUCUUUCCUGCCUAUAGAAAAUCUUUCUAAUUGCCAACAAGACUUUUAUUAAUUAAAACUGGACAUUAAGCUCUGUUGUCAUGAACAACUGGAAUGUAAACCACAGUAUUUUGGAGUGCAGAACAUUCUCAAUUAAGUGAUAAGUCCAAAUGAUGAAGGAAAUGUUUUAAUUCACAAAUGGAGAUUUGUAUGUGUUAUCAGGUUCACCUGCUUGAUAUUAGAUACAUUAAAGCACUGAAUUUUCAUGGAUAUUAGUUGGAUUUAUCAUUGAAAUAUGGUUAAGAUUACAAAUUAUGUGUUUUAUUUGUUGCUUUUUUUUAACCUUUUAAUGUAUAUUCUUGUCUUCAGAUGGUUUGCUAUUUUUCUCUCCUGGGGGUUUAUUCUAAGAUACCUUUGUAUUUUAUUUCAUGUGGAGAUCAUGAAAGUAGGAAAUAUACCUUUAGAAGUAACUCGCACCUUUCUUAUGAUGUUAAGAGAAACACUAGUGUUUAGUUUUACAGUAACCCUCAUAUUUUAAUGGUGUUACAGCAUUUGCAAAAAUUAUUCUGCUAAGUAUUUACAACUCUAUUUAUUAUUCACUCAAGUAUUAACAUUCUCUAUUAAAUAAGAGGAGGUGUUGUAAAGAGCUGCUAGUAGGUUCGCUUUAAACCACAUGAGCUUAACCAAGAAUAUGUUAUGAGAAGUUGCUGAUUAAAUCAGUGCUGUUUUUACACCACUUCUGGCCAACUCAGAAUAAUUUAGAUUGUUCUUUUAACAAAAAAGGCUUUCUAUCUCUUUUAAAGUAAGUCACUUUAUAAGUUGGCAGAAGUGAAUGACACUUUGAGAGUAGUCUUUCAAUCUGAAGAUGUAAGACUUCCUGAAACAAGUUCUCAAGAAGUCUUUACAUUAUAUUUAUAACUCAUAUAAAAAUUAUAUUUAGAAUUUUUAAACAUGUACAAAGGGCUACAUUUUAAUUUUAAAAUAGCUUCACAUUAUUUUACUUAUAUUGGGUUUUUCUUCAUUUUAAUCCUUUUCAAGUGGAAUGGCUUAGAAUAAGUAUACACUUGAAAUCUCCUCUACAUGAUCUUUGUUCUUUAACAGUGUAUACCAGAGGGUUAGUUGGGGAAAAACUUCAUUCUCAGGAAAAGACUUGAAUGAUUAUGUGACCCUGUUAUAUUUCAGUGUUGUGACAAAUGUGUAAACUAGCGGGGGAAGACAGUAUUGUAUCAUAAAUGAGAUGCGUAGUUUGUUUUCUUUCAUGGGAAGUAGAGAUAAAAAUAUAUACAUUUCUCUAAUUGAGUUGUUUAGAGAAAGAACUAAUGUCUCAUAUGAUGUAUUUACUUAUUUUAAAAAAAAGAAUAGGAAUGAGAUGUCCCUGAGCUGUACUUUUCUAUUAUUAUAAGGCCUUUAGGCAUCAGUGCAUCUGGGUUAUCAACAUUUUCUCAAAUGCUGUCAAUAUUUUACUGUAAUUUAUGUUCUUAUAUUUAUGUAUAUUUGUUAAAACUGUAAAAAAAUUUCACAGAUUUUUUUCCAAUACCUGUGCAAGAUACAUGUGUAGCUCAAAACUAUUUGUGAUCUACUGUUUGCAUGUAAGAGACCAGGAUAUGUAACUCUUAUAUUUUAAGUGUAUACAUAUUGUGUAUAUAACAUAUGGAUAUUAAAAAUGGGGAAUUGCACAUUUUACCUUUUGGACAGUAAUUUCUAUCACAGUUAGAAGGAAAUGAUAGUCAAAUACACGUUUAGAUUAAAACUAGUUUAAAAAAUUAUAAAUGAAUCUAAUCAAAAUGUGAAUAGUAGUCAAAAGGAUAAUUUAAUAAGCAUUUUACGUUACUAAAUUUGUUCAUUUCAAUAUUAACUAAAUUUCCCUCAUCAAAGCAAUCUUUGUGAUAUUACUUCGCUAUUAAAUAAAGAAAAUUGGAUGCAAGACAAUGGAGAAACUUUAAAACUAAACAGGACCACCCUUUAUUCUUAAAUUUGUGUGUGUCCAACAGUUGAAUUGAAUGUCUAUAAGGUCUAAAGGUAGAAUGUGAAUAUUGCCACAGAGUUCAUUGCUCUCAGUAUAAGAUUUUACUUUAUUAAUGCAGAAGGAAUAUGGAUAUAUUUCUUUAAGUCUGCAGAUUUUUUUAUUAUGGUGCAGCUUUUUUUUAAUUAUGUUUUUAAAAUUAUACAGUUGAAAAAUAUGCCAUUUCAUAAAGUCUGAGGAUUUUCGUCAACCUUACUGAAACACACUGGUGCUUUCAUCAUCAGAGGUCAAAUUAUUAUGAUAACUAUUCCAUUAAGUUUGCCAAACAUUUGUCGUGGUUACCAGUGCAGCCUGUCAAAUUCUGCUAUUUGACACAGCUUUGGAAAGAUUUAGUUCUUGGUUUUUCCGUUUUGUAUUAGAAUGACUGUUACAGUUUUAUUUGGCUGUUUAAAGCCAAAUUCAGCUAUUUAAUUAUGGUUUCAUGGACACUGUUGAGCAAUGUACAGUGUAUGGUGUGCUUACCUGUCCACUCUAGAGCAUUGCUUACAGGUUUUUUGUUUUUUAAGAUGCUGUGCUGUAAAAUACUGUCAUACUUGCUAUUUCCUGGUACAGUGUAGUUUUUCCCCUUUCAUUUGAAUAAAAGCAUGGCACCAAA